AAUCACGUGGCUGCCACCCAGGUAAGAAGAGGCCGCUCUUCCUGGGGUUGUUUCUCCGUGUGACGUGUGGCCUUUGAGAUCAACUCUCCUGUACCAGCGUAGGCCGCAUGAGUGGGGGGCGGGCUCCCGCGGUCCUGCUCGGCGGAGUGGUGAGUGACCGGCCCCGCCCCGCCCCUUCCGGUCCUCGAAGCCUCGACCGCUACCCGCACCCUAAAUCCCAGAGGUUGGCCCCCUGAGGUGUGAGUGAAAUGAGCUUUUGCUUUAUUUUCCAAGUUUCUCUCUCACCUUCAGGGGCAUUCUUCGGGGGUGCAUCAGAGGGAGGGCAGAGCCUGAGGAUCUAAGCGAAGGCUUCCCCGGGUGUAAUUUCCUGGGCUGUUUGUGAGGAGAGAUCGAAUUCGCCUCCUGCUCUCAGGCCUCUCUGCUCCUGUCUUUUGUUUGGAUGCCGGCGCUGCUGCCUGUGGCCUCCCGCCUUUUGUUGCUACCCCGAGUCUUGCUGACCAUGGCCUCUGGAAGCCCUCCGACCCAGCCCUCGCCGGCCUCGGAUUCCGGCUCUGGCUACGUUCCGGGCUCGGUCUCUGCAGCCUUUGUUACUUGCCCCAACGAGAAGGUCGCCAAGGAGAUCGCCAGGGCCGUGGUGGAGAAGCGCCUAGCAGCCUGCGUCAACCUCAUCCCUCAGAUUACAUCCAUCUAUGAGUGGAAAGGGAAGAUCGAGGAAGACAGUGAGGUGCUGAUGAUGAUUAAAACCCAAAGUUCCUUGGUCCCAGCUUUGACAGAUUUUGUUCGUUCUGUGCACCCUUACGAAGUGGCCGAGGUAAUUGCAUUGCCUGUGGAACAGGGGAACUUUCCGUACCUGCAGUGGGUGCGCCAGGUCACAGAGUCAGUUUCUGACUCUAUCACAGUCCUGCCAUGAUGAGCCCUGUUCCUGCUCAUCAUGAAGAUCCCCGCGAUACUUCAACGCCUUCUGACUUCCAGGUGAUGACUGGGCCCCCAAUAAAUCCCGUCUUUGGGUCUCUCUGCCUUUUGCCUGUUUUUUGUCAUGUAUGCAAAUUUGUUGGGAGAAUAUAAGUGCUUCUAGUCCCUGUAUUCUCUACAUCUUUCAGAAUGACUCAGAGCUGCUA